ACUGUUUUGCAAACAUAGCAUCAACAUAGAAGUUAUUUUGUAGGCUCCAGGAUGCAGCGAUGGGCUGCACUGCCAGCAUUGUUCUGCUUCAAGCUUUUCGUUCUGUGGUCCAGAGGAGCUGUCCACACAUUUGUAGACGACGCCAAGAGGAACCAUCCCACGAAAUUUUGCCUCUGGAAAGUGACGAUGAAAUGAAUAGACCCAGAACCCUCAUCAUAAUGCAAGAAAAGCCUAGGCUUCUCGAGCCUUUGGAUUAUGAGACUGUCAUUGAAGAACUUGAAAAGACCUACCGGAAUGAUCCUCUUCAAGAUCUCUUGUUCUUCCCCAGUGAUGACUUUUCAGCAGCCACAGUUUCCUGGGAUAUCCGCACGUUGUACUCAACAGUACCUGAAGAUGCAGAGCACAAGGCAGAAAAUUUACUGGUUAAGGAGGCUUGUAAAUUUUAUAGUUCCCAGUGGCAUGUGGUAAACUACAAAUAUGAACAAUAUUCUGGAGACAUUCGACAGCUACCCCGAGCAGAAUACAAACCAGAGAAGCUUCCUUCACAUUCCUUUGAGAUUGACCAUGAAGAUGCUGAUAAGGAUGAAGAUACCACUUCCCACUCGUCUUCCAAGGGGGGUGGAGGAGCGGGAGGAACUGGUGUUUUCAAGUCCGGCUGGCUCUACAAGGGGAAUUUUAACAGCACCGUGAACAACACCGUUACUGUUCGGUCAUUCAAAAAGCGCUACUUCCAGCUGACUCAGUUACCAGAUAACUCCUACAUUAUGAACUUUUACAAAGAUGAGAAAAUAUCCAAAGAACCCAAAGGAUGCAUCUUUUUGGAUUCCUGUACAGGAGUGGUGCAGAAUAACAGACUAAGAAAAUAUGCCUUUGAAUUGAAAAUGAAUGAUCUGACCUAUUUUGUGCUGGCAGCUGAAACAGAGUCAGAUAUGGAUGAAUGGAUCCACACCCUCAACCGCAUUCUGCAAAUCAGUCCUGAGGGGCCCCUCCAAGGGAGGAGGAGCACAGAGCUCACUGAUCUGGGUCUGGAUUCGCUGGAUAAUUCUGUAACUUGUGAAUGCACGCCAGAGGAAACAGAUUCUUCAGAGAACAACCUACACGCAGACUUUGCAAAGUACCUCACAGAAACAGAAGAUACUGUAAAAACAACUCGAAACAUGGAGAGGCUAAAUCUGUUCUCUCUAGAUCCAGACAUAGAUACCUUGAAACUUCAAAAAAAAGAUCUCUUGGAACCUGAGUCUGUGAUCAAACCAUUUGAAGAAAAAGCUGCCAAGAGAAUCAUGAUCAUCUGUAAAGCCCUCAACUCAAAUCUUCAGGGAUGUGUUACGGAGAAUGAAAAUGAUCCGAUAACGAAUAUUGAGCCUUUUUUUGUGAGUGUGGCACUUUAUGACCUCAGAGACAGCAGGAAGAUUUCUGCUGAUUUUCAUGUGGAUCUAAACCAUGCUGCUGUCAGACAGAUGCUCUUGGGGGCUUCUGUGGCUUUGGAAAAUGGCAACAUCGACACCAUCACUCCAAGACAAUCAGAAGAACCUCACAUCAAGGGACUUCCAGAGGAAUGGCUAAAAUUUCCAAAGCAGGCUGUAUUUUCUGUAAGCAAUCCACAUUCUGAAAUUGUUUUGGUGGCCAAAAUCGAAAAAGUCUUGAUGGGAAACAUUGCAAGUGGUGCCGAACCUUAUAUUAAGAACCCAGACUCCAACAAGUAUGCACAAAAGAUACUAAAAUCCAACAGACAAUUCUGCAGCAAAUUGGGAAAAUACCGUAUGCCUUUUGCUUGGGCAGUAAGAUCAGUAUUUAAGGACAACCAGGGAAAUGUGGACAGAGACUCAAGAUUUUCACCAUUGUUUAGACAAGAAAGUAGCAAGAUUUCAACUGAGGACCUAGUUAAACUAGUAUCAGAUUAUAGAAGGGCCGACAGAAUAAGCAAAAUGCAGACCAUUCCUGGAAGCCUGGAUAUUGCUGUUGACAACGUUCCCUUGGAGCAUCCAAAUUGUGUAACAUCGUCCUUUAUCCCUGUCAAGCCUUUCAACAUGAUGGCUCAAACAGAACCCACAGUGGAGGUGGAAGAAUUUGUUUACGAUUCAACAAAGUAUUGUCGGCCUUACAGAGUAUAUAAAAAUCAAAUUUAUAUUUACCCCAAACACCUCAAGUAUGAUAGCCAGAAAUGCUUCAACAAGGCACGGAAUAUAACUGUGUGCAUUGAAUUCAAAAAUUCAGAUGAAGAAAGUGCCAAGCCCCUGAAGUGUAUUUAUGGAAAACCUGGAGGGCCCCUCUUCACCUCAGCCGCCUACACAGCAGUUCUGCACCACUCUCAGAAUCCGGAUUUCUCAGAUGAGGUGAAAAUUGAGCUACCAACACAACUCCAUGAGAAACACCAUAUUUUGUUUUCUUUUUAUCACGUCACCUGUGACAUCAAUGCAAAAGCUAAUGCCAAAAAGAAGGAGGCUCUGGAAACGUCAGUUGGAUAUGCUUGGCUUCCUCUGAUGAAACACGAUCAGAUAGCUUCUCAAGAGUACAACAUCCCAAUAGCAACAAGUCUGCCUCCUAAUUAUUUAAGCUUUCAAGAUUCUGCAAGUGGAAAGCAUGGUGGGAGUGACAUUAAAUGGGUUGAUGGUGGCAAACCACUUUUCAAAGUGUCGACAUUUGUUGUAUCAACAGUAAAUACUCAGGAUCCACAUGUGAAUGCAUUUUUCCAAGAGUGCCAAAAAAGAGAGAAAGAUAUGUCUCAGUCACCUACCUCAAAUUUCAUCCGCUCUUGUAAGAACUUAUUGAAUGUGGAAAAGAUUCAUGCAAUCAUGAGUUUUCUGCCUAUAAUUUUGAAUCAGCUCUUCAAAGUUCUGGUACAGAAUGAGGAAGAUGAAAUAACUACAACUGUCACCAGGGUUCUGACCGACAUUGUGGCCAAGUGCCAUGAGGAGCAGCUGGAUCAUUCUGUCCAGUCAUAUAUUAAGUUCGUGUUCAAGACCAGGGCAUGCAAGGAGAGGACUGUACAUGAGGAACUGGCUAAAAAUGUGACUGGUCUUUUGAAAUCAAAUGACUCAACAACAGUAAAGCAUGUCCUAAAGCAUUCCUGGUUCUUCUUUGCAAUUAUCCUAAAAUCGAUGGCACAGCACUUGAUUGACACAAAUAAAAUCCAGCUUCCCCGGCCUCAGAGAUUUCCUGAAUCUUACCAAAAUGAAUUGGACAAUCUUGUCAUGGUCCUAUCCGACCAUGUGAUUUGGAAAUACAAGGAUGCACUUGAAGAAACAAGAAGGGCAAACCACAGCGUUGCCAGAUUUCUCAAGCGCUGCUUUACAUUUAUGGACCGAGGGUAUGUGUUUAAGAUGGUCAACAAUUACAUCAGCAUGUUCUCCUCCGGUGACCUUAAGACCUUGUGCCAGUAUAAAUUUGAUUUUCUUCAAGAAGUAUGUCAACAUGAACACUUUAUCCCUUUGUGUCUGCCCAUAAGAUCAGCAAACAUUCCAGAUCCUUUGACACCUUCAGAAUCGACUCAAGAGUUACAUGCAUCAGAUAUGCCUGAAUAUUCAGUCACAAAUGAAUUUUGUCGCAAACACUUCUUAAUCGGAAUUCUGCUCCGAGAAGUUGGCUUUGCCCUGCAGGAAGACCAAGAUGUCAGACACUUAGCUUUAGCUGUCCUAAAAAAUCUAAUGGCUAAGCAUUCAUUUGAUGAUCGAUACAGAGAGCCAAGAAAGCAGGCCCAGAUAGCAAGUUUAUACAUGCCCCUGUACGGCAUGCUCCUGGACAAUAUGCCAAGGAUUUAUCUGAAGGACCUGUAUCCUUUUACUGUCAAUACAUCUAAUCAGGGGUCUAGAGAUGAUCUAAGCACCAAUGGAGGAUUUCAAAGCCAGACAGCUAUCAAACAUGCAAACUCUGUGGAUACAUCAUUUUCUAAAGAUGUUUUAAAUUCCAUAGCAGCAUUUUCAUCAAUAGCUAUUUCUACAGUAAACCAUGCUGACUCCAGAGCAUCUUUAGCAAGUCUUGACUCCAAUCCAAGUACCAAUGAGAAGAGCAGUGAGAAGACGGACAACUGUGAAAAGAUCCCAAGACCCUUGUCUUUGAUUGGCUCAACUCUUCGAUUUGACAAGUUAGAUCAAGCAGAAACCAGGAGUCUCCUGAUGUGUUUUCUUCACAUUAUGAAAACGAUUUCGUACGAGACUCUGAUUGCCUACUGGCAGAGAGCUCCCAGCCCAGAGGUGUCCGACUUCUUCAGCAUCUUGGACGUUUGUCUUCAAAAUUUCAGAUACCUAGGAAAACGCAACAUAAUAAGAAAAAUUGCUGCUGCAUUUAAAUUUGUGCAGUCCACCCAGAACAAUGGAACUCUCAAAGGAUCCAAUCCUUCCUGCCAGACAUCAGGUCUCUUGUCACAAUGGAUGCACUCCACUUCCAGUCAUGAAGGCCAUAAGCAGCACAGAUCACAAACUUUACCUAUAAUUCGAGGCAAAAAUGCACUUUCUAACCCCAAACUCUUACAGAUGUUAGACAAUACCAUGACCAGCAACUCCAAUGAAAUAGACAUCGUGCAUCAUGUAGACACUGAGGCCAAUAUAGCUACGGAGGUUUGCCUCACUAUUCUGGACCUGUUAUCCCUCUUCACACAGACUCAUCAGAGACAACUCCAACAAUGUGACUGUCAAAAUUCAUUGAUGAAAAGGGUCUUUGAUACCUACAUGCUCUUUUUCCAAGUCAAUCAGUCAGCCACAGCGCUGAAGCAUGUGUUUGCCUCCUUGAGACUGUUUGUAUGCAAGUUUCCUUCAGCGUUCUUUCAAGGGCCUGCUGACCUCUGUGGAUCAUUCUGUUACGAAGUCCUAAAAUGCUGUAACCACAGGUCACGGUCAACUCAGACAGAAGCCUCAGCCCUUCUGUACUUUUUCAUGAGGAAGAAUUUUGAAUUUAACAAGCAGAAGUCAAUUGUCCGGUCCCACUUACAACUCAUCAAAGCUGUGAGCCAGUUAAUAGCCGAUGCUGGGAUUGGAGGCUCUCGGUUUCAACAUUCGCUUGCAAUUACCAAUAAUUUCGCCAAUGGAGAUAAGCAAAUGAAAAACAGCAAUUUCCCAGCAGAGGUGAAGGACCUGACUAAGCGUAUAAGGACUGUUUUGAUGGCCACAGCUCAGAUGAAGGAGCACGAGAAGGACCCCGAGAUGCUGGUGGAUCUCCAGUACAGCCUGGCAAACUCCUACGCAAGCACUCCUGAACUACGCAGGACCUGGCUGGAAAGUAUGGCCAAGAUUCAUGCCAGAAACGGAGAUUUAUCUGAGGCUGCCAUGUGUUACAUCCAUAUUGCUGCUCUCAUUGCAGAGUAUCUGAAAAGAAAGGGUUACUGGAAAGUGGAAAAGAUUUGCACAGCAUCCCUGCUCUCGGAGGAUACCCACCCCUGUGAUAGCAACUCAUUACUAACAACUCCCAGUGGAGGAAGCAUGUUCUCUAUGGGAUGGCCAGCUUUUUUGAGCAUUACACCAAACAUUAAGGAAGAAGGAGCGAUGAAAGAGGAUUCUGGAAUGCAAGAUACACCAUACAAUGAGAAUAUCCUGGUGGAGCAGCUAUACAUGUGUGUGGAGUUUCUCUGGAAGUCUGAGCGAUAUGAACUCAUUGCUGAUGUCAACAAGCCCAUCAUUGCUGUCUUUGAGAAACAACGAGACUUCAAAAAAUUGUCAGAUCUCUACUACGACAUUCAUCGGUCAUAUCUGAAAGUGGCAGAGGUGGUGAAUUCGGAGAAGCGGCUGUUUGGUCGCUACUAUCGUGUGGCAUUUUAUGGGCAGGCUGUGGUAAGUUCUCACUCACUCUCGCUCUCCAUUUGCAUGCUCUAACACCCCUCACACUUCCCUCUGUAUGGUUUUACUGAACCUUAACCUUUUUGUGCAAAUCACCAUUUGGUACAAAGGGAGAGAUAAUCCUGCUUUCAUUCAUUUUUGGAGUCAUCCUGCAUUUCUUUAACUAAGUUGUGUUUAUGCCAGUUAUCUGAAUUACAAAAAUGUAUCCUUUGUUUUUCAUACAUGCUUUCUGCCUAAAGGUAGAUGUAGUCUGAAAGCCUUACAUACACAAACACACACAGAGAUAAGUAUGGGUACCACGUAUCUUAAAUAUAUGUAGCAUAGACUUGGUAUUGUAGAUCGUCUACUUAUUUCAGGCCACUAUGAGUUGCAGCUUAUUAAGGAGACCAGAAUGGUCAGAAUUUUGGAAGUUGGAGUGAUGGUUAUUGGUAAGCACCUCCCAAGAUAUUGAAAAAACUGUGUUUUUUCUGAAGGAGUGUCUUAGAGUGAUGGGGGUCUAUGGUGGUGAGCUCUAAGCAUUCUCAGAGGUGAUGGGACUAAUUCCAAACAUAAAAGAUGAACCAGGGAAUAAAUCUUUACCCAAUAUGUCUGGGUAAGUCUCCAGAGAUGGAGAAAGGAGCAAGGUAAGAAAUUUGGAGAACAAGCCAUGUCCAAAAUAACCUGCCAGUACCCAGAGCUCUAUGACAAAGGAUUUUCUUCAUAUUAUUUUGAGUCAUAUGAAAUUGCCUAUAUUCAACCACUUUUUUAUGUACAAAAAUGGCAACUUUAUAUGGUUCAACCUAAUUAUUGUCAGUUAAGCUGGAAAGAGAAAGCAUUUAAUAUCUACACAUUGUCCAUAUUCAGCCCUACUUGUCUGACCAGUACAUACUUUUUUGUAAUUCUUUAAAUUCCUUCCCACAUUCAUACCAUACCAGCAUUUUCUAUGUUCAUUUAUAAAUUUGGGAUUAUGGGCCCUUAACUCACCUACUAAAAGAAUACUUGAAAACCCCUGUACUAAAUAGACUGAGGGGGGGCAGUGGGGAAGUAUUGGGGGGAGCCCUUGCAAAUGACCUAACUUUAUUCUUCUUUCAGACUCCUCAGUAAAGUGUGCUGAUUUUACACCUGAUUUUUUUUUUAAUGCUGCAGUACUCUCACUUGUCUUUAUAAAAAAAUUCCAAGGCUGGGCGCGGUGGCUCACACCUGUAAUCCCAGCACUUUGGGAGGCCGAGGUGGGCAGAUCACAAGGUCAGGAGAUGAAGACCAUCCUGGCUAACACAGUGAAACCCUGUCUCUACUAAAAAUACAAAAAAUUAGUAGGACGUGGUGGCGAGCGCCUGUAAUCCCAGCUACUCGGGAGGCUGAAGCAGGAGAAUGGCGUGAACCCUGGAGGUGGAGCUUGCAGUGAGCCAAGAUCGUGCCACUGCACUCCAGCCUGGGAGACAGAGUGAGACUCUGCCUCAAGAAAAAAAAAAAAAAAAUUCCAGUCUGAGCUUAAAAGGCAAAGUGUUUUGUUAAAUUCUCUGACUGAGAACCUGCCUAAGCACGACACUCCAUAAGUUCAAACUCAGCCACCUUUGAACAAGGAGAACCAAUGGAGGUCAUCCUGAUAAGCAGCAAAUUAGAGCCUCAUUCAUCAUUGCUCAGAUGAGAUUCAAAUGCCUGUCUCAAGACACCACAUGGAGAGUGAGAACUAUGGGAUUCAACAGGAGCAGACAGCACAUAUCACUUCACAUUCCAUGAUAAAUAAAUACCAAGUAGACUUGAGCAUUCCCCCGAACGUGUACAGAAUGAAGGUUCCGAAGAUUUAAGAUAAAAUCUUGACUACUUGAUUAGCAUAAUCUCCAUGGUCAGAAAUGAUUUCUUAUUCAUAAUGGUGCUUUAUGUCCCUGUAAAACUUACCUUUUAAUAUCCAAGUUGACGUGUCUUGCAAUGAUGUUAAAAAGAUUAUGGAAAUAUGAUAUGCAAUAGGCUCUUUGCCUGCACAAAGGCCUUUGGGUACAAUUUUUUAGUGUCCCACGCAGACCACUGCUCUCAUUUUAUAGUUUUGGCUGGGGUAUUUAAUACUAAUUGUGUCUGUAAUGAGCCAGACACUAGAAAACAAGUUUAAAACUGAUCGUUCAUAGCAGGAACUUUAAAAAAAUGCAAGUCUUGCACAACAUGAAUUGUCUAAUGCAACACCCGGCAUCAGCAUCAAUAUGGAAAUUUGACAUAUAGCAGCCUAUACAAAGUGUCCUCCAAAGUGUCCCUGAGGUAUUGAUUUCCAUAGUAAUGAAACAGCAGCAGUGAGCAAACAUCGACUAUAAUCAAUGAAGUCCUUAGGCCCUGGUAUUUAACAUGAAAGCAAGUGAAUACCCAUUACAUAACUUAAAAUAUCAGAUGCCCCUGGAAUUAAUUAAGUAAAAGACCUGGAAGAAUUUUAUUCUAUCCACCAAAGGCCAUAGAUUCCAUAAUUUGCAGUCAUGCCUAUAUGGGUGUACUUGCAUCUCAGGAUCUUAAUAAAAAAGGAGUUUGGGGGAGGAGGGAAGGUGCAGGCGUAGUAUGGAAAACCAUCAUCUCCACUUUGGGACAUGAUAUAGCUCUCCACCUAUAGGAAAGUCGCUGAUCUAGGCCACAUAUCUAUACUGUAUAAUUAAAUGUCAUAAUUGAGUUCAGAUUUAUAUGCUAAGAGAAGCUACAUGAAUGCAGAGAAAUUCAUUCAUGUAGCUUCUCUUCUCUUAGCAUUUAGCCUAGUAUUGACAUUUUCUGGCCUGUCUUUUGUAUACUAGAUUCCUCCUCAAAUACAUUCUUCUCUUUGUGAACUUUGAAUGAGUCUAAUAAAAUACCAGGGGCCCUAAUAUUUGACAACACAGUGAUGAUCCAGGGACAUUGCAAGAUUCUGAAGUACCUGCAAAAGCAUCUGAGGAGGAGUCAAUGCUUUUAGUUGUCAGUUUAUUGAAGUACAUUUUUACCAUAAUGUAUUGCCUUAAAGUUUCAUAAUCCAUGCAGUCCUUGUUUAACUAGUGUGUGUUCUUUCUUGACCAGAGCAGAAGAAGGUGUUUACUGCAUUGCAAAAUGACAUUUUAAAAAUCAAACUAGCAAGGGAAGUGCAGAGAUCACAUUUCCCAUUGCCUUGAAAUGCAGUCAGCUUAUAACCUUGGGGCUAAAGCAAAAGAGAAACUGACCCUGGUUUUCAUAACUCUGUGUCCCUGUUUGUAAAUCAUUUAUAUCAUAGACAGAGCUGAAAUUGAAGCCUUCCUUCAGAUAGUGUCUGUAGCUCAGUGGGCUUUGCUUUGAUAGUUUCCCUGGGUAUAAGGUAAGCAUGCAUUCCAAACAUUUUCAGAGCUGCCAUUUGUCUGGCUUCAAAACUCUUUACAGAAACCCCAGUGGACAGCAGAGUAAAUGGUUUAUUCUGCUCCUCCAUCUCCUUCUUAUUCAUUUUACAAAACAGGUUUACAUUUCCAAGCUCUUUAGAAAAAGGUUCCAAUCACCAAUUGAUCACUUGCCAAAAUAUUGUAAUGAGCUUCAACAGACCUUUUAUAAUAAGAAAAACUCAGUUGCCCAGGCAAGAGAAGCUGAAAGUAUGUAUUUUCGAGCACUGAAAACUGAGUUAAGCUGCAUAAAAGCCAGAACUCAAAUUGCUUUAUAGAUACAGAGAUUUUUCAUCAUUGUUGUCAUCACCACCAGCGUCAUGAUCAUUACCAUCCUCAACAUAGCUAGCACUCACCAAAGGCCAUCUGUUUACCAAGCGCGGUCCUUACAGCCUCCCAGUAAGUAGGUUGCUGAGUCUGAAUUUUCCCAUCCCACAGCCCAAGGAGGAGGGAUGAAAGAAAGUCACAGGUUAUGAGCAAGGCCGCAAUACAUUUUUUUUUUUUUUAGACAGAGUCUCACUGUGUCACCCAGGCUGGAGUGCAGUGGCUCGAACUUGGCUCACUGCAACCUCCGCCUCCUGGAUUCAAGCGAUUCUCCUGCCUCAGCCUCCUGAGUAGCUGGGACUACAGGCGUGUGUCACCAUGCCCAGCUAAUUUUUGUAUUUUUAGAGAGACGGGGUUUCACUGUGUUGGCCAGGAUGGUCUCGAUCUCUUGUACUUUGUGAUCCGCCCACCUCGGACUCCCAAAGUGCUGGGAUUGCAGGCGUGAACCACCGCACCCAGCCGAUGAUGACAAUUUUUACCUGCCUCCCACCACUCAUUUUCUGCUCACUCUAGAUUCGGAAAUUUGUCAGGGGAAAAAUUUUACAGUGAAAAUGUGUCUUUGUACUAGUUUUCACACUAUGGUGAAAAAGAAAAAAUCUUUUCCUGAACCUUAGAGACAUUUUUCUACUUGAAAUUGAAGUUGCAAAUGUUGCUUCAGCUUUAGCCCCAUGAGGAUUCGCCUGAAAGCUUCAGAAGCCUUAUUUCUCUGAUGUGUCAGUCUGUCAAUUGUAGCCACUAACUCCUGACCUUGAAUCAGACAAAACUCCACAAAGACAGCAACAGAAAAAAAACAUAGCAGGCUGGAAGUCAUGUGGGAGUGGAGUCAGACCUCACUACCCCUACAAAGUCUACAGGAAUGACAGGAGCUGCUUUACAUGCUUUCAACAUCAUAUGACACUUUGUAGCAGUUUGGGGUCAAGGCAUUUAUAAUUACUUGCAUUUUGUCUUGAACAUUUCUCGAAGAAAUUGUUCAAUAAAAACAUCUUUAUUUAAAGCCGUGGACUAUUUUCCAGUUAUGCCUGGUACACAUACGCCUUUUUAAGAUGUGUGCCCUUUAAGAACUCUUUCAUUCAUCUGCUUGUUCAACAAAUAGAGUGACCUCCUCCUAAAGACCAGGCAUUGUGCUAAACACUGGGCAUGCAAUGUUGAAGACACAUUUCCCACCUUUAGAAAGCCCAAAGUCAAUUAGGGAGAUGUGCAAGGAAGCAGGUGAUUACCUGAUUGCCAAGAAUUCUGCUAUGGAGUAGACCUUGUUCAUUGGCUUCUGCAAAGGUACAGCCACAGCCCACUUAGAAUAAAAAUUACCCUGUUAAAGAUGAUCCUAUUUACAUGUAUGAAAGUGCUUUUGAAGUAUAAAGCAUCAUACAGAUGUGAGUUUAAUCAAUAUUCUUAUAUUGUCUCACCAUGAAAAAAUAAUAGCACUGGAACACUUUGCCUAUGCUUUUUUUAACAAUUAAUAUUUUUAAAUAGUCAAAACUGAUUUUUUAAUAUGGGUAAGUUUCCUUUUGACAUCCAGUGUCUUCACCCAGACCUCAAAAGGCAUUUCCUUAUGGGUCAACUCUACAAUUAGAAGAAACCAGAUAUAGCCUGUAAUCCCAGCACUUUAGGAGGCCGAGGUGGGUGGAUCAUCUGAGGUCAAGAGUUUGAGACCAGCCUGGCCAACAUGGCGAAACUCCACCUUAAUUAAAAACACAAAAAUUAGCCGGGCGUGGUGGUACACAUCUGCAGUCCCAGCUACUUGGGAGGCCAAAGUAGGAGAAUCGCUUGAACCCAGGAGGCAGAGGUUGCAGUGAGCCAAGGUCACACCUCUGCACUCCAGCCUGGGCAACAGAGCAAGACUCUGCCAAAAAAAAAAAAAGAAACCAGAUAUCCUUGGGUUCUUAACUCCGAACUUAAUCUAGUAUUCUGAGGCCACAUGUAUUCCACAGGAAAUAUGCUUCUGUGUCUCUUCAAAGAGAAGGAAUUAUAAAGAUUGCUUCACUUAGUUAUCUGCAGCUAAUAGAAUCUUCCCUUCCCCCUGCUUCAAACCAGACAAAUAAAUUAAUAGAGGCUAAAACCUACUUGCUCUUGUGGAAUAAAAAUGAUGAUAUGAUUGCUAUUUUUAAUCCUAUAAUGUCUUCCUUUUCAAGAAUGUAAAAGAUCUCUUAGUAAGGUGAAUUGCAUGAUUAAGUUACAUAUAGGUAAGUUUCAGGAGGUCCCUGAAGUCAUGUUGAUGUAAAGUUAUUUUUUAAAUAGCAGUACUUGGGAGCAUAACACAUGUAAUUUCUGUUACGACAACUACAUAAAGUGUUGUGGUUUUUCAUCUAAGAUUAUGUGGGAUGCACGUCAGCCCAUUUAAAUAGCUUUACAUGCCAUACACCAUUUCUUAUGUUAGUUUCAAAGACUUACAGGAGAUCUUAUUAAAAAUGAUACUGACUGCUCUUUGAAUGCUGCCAAAAAUUGCUCCAUAUUUCGUGUUCUACCCCAAGCUGCCACAAGAGGGCAUUCUUCCCCCAAAAUAUAUGCAAGUAGGUAGUACCAUUGAGUUCUACAAAUAGAGAAAAUAAUAUUUGUAAGAUAUUUCAUGAGUUUCUUUGGCCUGGCUAGGAAAUAUUUACAUUAAUGUCUGAUUAUAAGAUGAUACUUUAUUUUCUCACUGUGUUUUCUUCUCCGAUUUUGAAUUUUAUAGGGUGUUAACCAAUGGAUUAGAUGACAACCAAAAACUGUAUAUGUUUUUUAAGUAAAUGGCUUUUUGUUUUGCUUUUGAUUUAUGAUUAGCAUUGUCUAAUAAAAUUGGUGGUUCAUUAUGUUCCAUAG